CUCCGCAGCCGCCGACGCGGGAGUGUGGAGAGGCCGAGAGGAGCCUUCCGCCCCCCGCCCCGGGACAUUGCGCUAGAGGCCGAGGCCCGGAGUCUUACGGCGGCGGGAUGUCCUGGGAAAAUGUAGCUGUGGAAGAGCAGAACAUUCCUCCCUCCUGUGAUGGCUGACAUUCAUAGGAAGGCGGACACACGGAAGACGCCAGGUAACAAGAGCCCAGAAGAAGGCCGGCGUGGCCGGGCUUUCCUGCCUUAGUCCACAGGCUCCUCAGAAGUCAGGGCCCAUAUCUUCCCCGCAUUCUCCUUGGCUGGGGGAAGGGAGAGCCCCCAAUGGCCCCCAAAAAGCCAGAGCCCAAGAAGGAUGAUGCCAAGGCAGCCCCCAAGGCAGCUCCAGCUCCCGCACCUCCCCCUGAGCCUGAGCGCCCUAAGGAGGUCGAGUUUGAUGCUUCCAAGAUCAAGAUUGAGUUCACACCUGAGCAGAUUGAAGAGUUCAAGGAAGCCUUCAUGCUGUUCGACCGCACACCCAAGUGUGAGAUGAAGAUCACCUACGGGCAGUGUGGGGAUGUCCUGCGGGCGCUGGGCCAGAACCCCACACAGGCAGAAGUGCUCCGUGUCCUGGGGAAGCCAAGACAGGAAGAGCUCAAUACCAAGAUGAUGGACUUUGAAACUUUCCUGCCUAUGCUCCAGCACAUUUCCAAGAACAAGGACACAGGCACCUAUGAGGACUUCGUGGAGGGGCUGCGGGUCUUCGACAAGGAGGGCAAUGGCACUGUCAUGGGUGCUGAGCUUCGCCACGUGCUGGCCACGCUGGGUGAGAGGCUGACAGAAGACGAAGUGGAGAAGUUGAUGGCUGGGCAAGAGGACUCCAAUGGCUGCAUCAACUAUGAAGCAUUUGUGAAGCACAUCAUGUCCAGCUAAACCUCGUGCCCAGGAAGCCCAGGGAAGGCUGUGCAGGGACGUCUCAUCUCCCAUGUGUGAUGCUGACACCAGCGGCCUGGAGUCGUGGGAAGGAGGGGAGCCUUACCAAGACUCCUGCAAAAACCCUUGGACCUCUCCACGUGGUUGCCGUCUCUGGCCCCUCUCAGGCUGUGCUUACCUGUGACAGCAGCUCUGUCCCCACCCCAUGGGCCUCAUGAAUAAAUGGCUUCUUGCCGGCCUUCC